AAGCUACUCAGAUAAGAGGCUCCAAGAGGACAUUUUUGGAUGUGAAAAACAAUGAGAAGGAGGACAACACACAUUUACAAUCGUCUUAAUUUUGUACUCAGAAAAAGGAUGUGAAGACAAUGCACAGGGAAUACAAUAGUUUCAGAUCUGUGUACAGUUUCCUUUUGCUUCAUCUCCUGCAACAAUGUAAUGAAGACACCAUGAUAUCAUUAACAUUUCACACAAAAGGAAAAUGAGGCUGAAAUGGUGUGGGCAAGGCCCAGGAAUCUGGAGCAUCCCUAACCAAGCAGGAGAGCACCUGGGAUAGAGAAAGUGCUCAAGAAUGUUCACUUACUGAUUACUACAAUCAAAAAAAGAUACGACACUAAUUUACCACAUUCUUCUUACUUAUUUUAUGAGAUACUAUUCUUCCAAGGUGGAGAAAGUGGAGAAAGUAGAGUGACGCAGCUAAGGGAGUAAAUCGACCCUCAGCCAACAAGUGGCAAAAGCCUGAAGAAAGUGAUCAAGAUCACUGAUGACCCCGCUGCCCAUCUCCAAGGGGGCGGGUAUCACAACCCCGACGCCACACCACGUAUCAUUCCGCAAAACUCCCGCGCCUCCCACGCAGAACUGGCAAGAGGGAAGGCGAGACAGCAGUGAACAGCUGGUACGCAGCACCCACAGCACCGCGGCAGCAGCUAGUGCCGACUCCCGCCUAGCUCUUUUGACUCUGUUCGCGGGAAGAAUGGGGAAACAGUAAGGUUGCGGCGCCUCCCGCGAGACGAGGUACCUGAGGCUGGCCCCGCAGUCCCCCGCCGCACCAGCACCGGAGCUUCACACCCCACUUCCGGGGUCAAGUCACCGCCGGGAAUCCUGUGAUCGCAGAAAGGUAGUCUCAGGUUCCGCCCCUAUCCAAGUCCCGCCUCCACUGCCUCUCGCCCUGUAUCUGUCAACUUCCGGGACGCCGCGCGUCACUAAGCAGCCAAUCUCCACUUCCGGACUCAUCCAGCCCCUUCUCCACCCCUUUCAGAGACAGCGCGAUUGCGAUUUAGGUUUCCGCGCAUUUAAUUGGCGAAGCUGGAGCGCUAGUCUUCGCUGAUUGGUGCCGAGAAAUCUGCCCCAUAGACACCCGCGGGGCGCACAGUUUCAGUCGUCCGUGGGUUUCCCGCCAGCCGCAGUCUUGGACCAUAAUCAUGGUGGACAUGAUGGACUUGCCCAGGUCGCGCAUCAACGCCGGCAUGCUAGCUCAAUUCAUCGACAAGCCUGUCUGCUUCGUAGGGAGGCUGGAAAAGAUUCAUCCCACCGGAAAAAUGUUUAUUCUUUCAGAUGGAGAAGGAAAAAAUGGAACCAUCGAGUUGAUGGAACCCCUUGAUGAAGAAAUCUCUGGAAUUGUGGAAGUGGUUGGAAGAGUAACCGCCAAGGCCACCAUCUUGUGUACAUCUUAUGUCCAGUUUAAAGAAGAUAGCCAUCCUUUUGAUCUUGGACUUUACAAUGAAGCUGUGAAAAUUAUCCAUGACUUCCCUCAGUUUUAUCCUUUAGGGAUUGUGCAACAUGAUUGAUCUUGAUGGAUUUUCAUACGAUUGUAAAUGAGCUAUAUUAAAGUCUAUUAAAGGAAGCCCUUCUUGUUUGAGGGAGAGAUUUCUGUGCUUUCUCAUAUUUAAUUUGCUGUUUUUAAGAUAUUCCAACCUAGAGUUUUUGAUGGAACUGAUAUAUUGACAGUUCUCACCGAAGUCCUUUUAUAAAGAAUUGCUACUCCAAUAUAUGGUCAGAUUAGAUGCAAGAAUAAAGCAGUUGUCCGAGUCUAAGUUUCUAUUUUAUUAAUAAAAACUAAAAUGGUACGUACUAUCGGUCAUUUCAUUUUCAUUCUUUUAAUCAUGUAUUCAAGCACAAACUUGAAAUUUCAUAGCCAUAAGGUCAAGAUUUAGACCUACCAAAUAAAACCUUGGGCCAGCUGUGUUAAGGAUUUGCUCACCUUUUCCCAAACUAUACCUUGAUAAUUAUUUCCUUGAUACCCUACUUACAAAAUGAAGUAGAUGACAUU